CUGGAUGCACAUUGCUAAGUUCUCACUCCCGUAUUUUUUUAAACCAAAAAUGACCACCACAGGGUCACCCAAACAACAAAACACUCACAGCUUCUGUUGAGCUGAUGGUUGGAAAAUAAGCAGCAAGAAAGAGACAAGAUUAGGGUCUUGGGCUUUUUAGAGUCAAACUCAUGCCUUGUUCCAGAACACAAGGCAGACAGUCAAGUCAGCAAAUAUUCACGGAGCAUCUCCUCUUCCUGGGGCGAGGAGCUGGACCCGGCCUCUGUCCGGAAGGGGCAUUUCCUGCCUCAGCACAGGCGCUACAGCUUUGCUCUCAGUCCCCUAAGUAAAGGAGCUGCUCAGCCUUGACUAGCCUACAACAGCCAGGGCUUUCCGGUAGAUUCUGGCACUUUCUAUGCCCCACCCCUUGUGGUUUCUUAGGGCUGCUGAAAUGAAUGACCACACACCUGGCGGCUUAAACAACACAAAUGUCUUAUCCUACAGUACUGUGGGACAGAGCUCCAGCAAAGGCCUUCUGGGGCUGAAUUCAGGGUGCAGCAGGUCUGCGUUCCUACUGGACGCUCUAGGGGAAAAUUAUUUGCCUUUCCACUUCCAGCUUCUAGAAACUUCUCUGGGCCCCUGCCUUCAUCUUCAAAGCCAGCUAUGUUGCGUCUCUUUGCCUUUCCUCUGCAGUCACUUCUCCCUCUGCCUGACUUCCUGCUUCCCUCCACCCCUCUCAAGGGCCUCAGUGAUUCCACUGGCCCCUCAGAAAAGCCAGCAUCACGUUCCCACUCUGAGGGCAGUGCUUAGCAACCCAAAUUCCAUCUCCAAAGCCCCCCUUUCCUUGCAAGCUAAAAUAUUCGCAGGUUCUGGGGACAUGGCCCAUUGGAACUUGGACCUCUUUGGGGGCUAUUGUCCUGCCCACCACGGGGGGUUAGCCUUGGACACUGUUUUCUUCCGAUUUCUCCUGGACGAGAGCAGAAACAAGCUCAGUGAAGUGACUCUCCUGAGGUCACAAAUGCUGGAUAGAGUCAGAGCCAAUGCUUCUGACUCUAUCUGUUGCUGAGCUCUGUGUAGACAAAAUAAACCAUCUGCCGGCUGAUGUCACAAGGGCUGCCCCGCUCGGCAGCCUCAGUGAGCUCCUCUCUAGAAUGGGGAUGAGGAUAUCCACUUGGAAGCCUGCUCCUCCCAGCCCGGUCCCCAGCUCACACUGGAUGCUGACUAAGUGUUUCCCCUUUUCCUUUCCACUCUCUUUCUUUCCACCAGAAUGUGGUGACAGAUCUAUUUUCGAGGGAAGAACUCGGUAUUCCAGAAUCACAGGGGGGAUGGAGGCGGAGGUGGGUGAGUUUCCGUGGCAGGUGAGUAUUCAGGCAAGAAGUGAACCUUUCUGUGGCGGCUCCAUCCUCAACAAGUGGUGGAUUCUCACUGCGGCUCACUGCUUAUAUUCCGAGGAGCUGUUUCCAGAAGAACUGAGUGUCGUGCUGGGGACCAACGACUUAACUAGCCCAUCCAUGGAAAUAAAGGAGGUCGCCAGCAUCAUUCUUCACAAAGACUUUAAGAGAGCCAACAUGGACAAUGACAUUGCCUUGCUGCUGCUGGCUUCGCCCAUCAAGCUCGAUGACCUGAAGGUGCCCAUCUGCCUCCCCACGCAGCCCGGCCCUGCCACAUGGCGCGAAUGCUGGGUGGCAGGUUGGGGCCAGACCAAUGCUGCUGACAAAAACUCUGUGAAAACGGAUCUGAUGAAAGCGCCAAUGGUCAUCAUGGACUGGGAGGAGUGUUCAAAGAUGUUUCCAAAACUUACCAAAAAUAUGCUGUGUGCCGGAUACAAGAAUGAGAGCUAUGAUGCCUGCAAGGGUGACAGUGGGGGGCCUCUGGUCUGCACCCCAGAGCCUGGUGAGAAGUGGUACCAGGUGGGCAUCAUAAGCUGGGGAAAGAGCUGUGGAGAGAAGAACACCCCAGGGAUAUACACCUCGUUGGUGAACUACAACCUCUGGAUCGAGAAAGUGACCCAGCUAGAGGGCAGGCCCUUCAAUGCAGAGAAAAGGAGGACUUCUGUCAAACAGAAACCUAUGGGCUCCCCAGUCUCGGGAGUCCCAGAGCCAGGCAGCCCCAGAUCCUGGCUCCUGCUCUGUCCCCUGUCCCAUGUGUUGUUCAGAGCUAUUUUGUACUGAUAAUAAAAUAGAGGCUAUUCUUUCAA